GGGUCGAGCAGGCCACAUCUGGCCCUCAAGGAUGCGUAAUCAUGAAACUUUGCAGAACUUCUCUAGAACAAUCAGAAGUUCUGACCCCAUUGGGCCUGUCUUCCCCCACGUGGAGCUGGGUCGUGGCUGUCCUCUUCAGCUGGGACACAUGCUCUCGGGUCAGCCUCAGCUCCACCUGCCCGGCUUCACUCACUACCACGCCUCUUCUGUAGACACCCUGCACAUGGCUAAGGCUCCCCAGACAUUCCCAAGAAGUCAGGACUGGACCCCAGGUUGGCGAAGCAGUGCACCCUCGGUGGCACCCCACUGCCUUUCCUGGUGCUGUGGCCUCUGCUGCAGAUCACAGAUUCAUGGCCUUCUGUCUGUCCCUCUUCUCCAAUCCCAGCUGUUCCUUCUGUAAAUCUGUCCCCCAGGGCAGGUCCCUCCCCCAAAGGCCCCAUUCAUACUGGUGUUGGUCAGUCACCCAGUGUUUGCUCACCCAGGCCACCCUUUAUCCAGUCAAGCCACCCUCCACUGCUCCUGCAGGACUCUAGAGCCAGGUGGCCUGGGCUGAAAUCUUGCUGUGUCACUUACAACCCGGGUGAUCCUGGGCCGAUGACUCAUCUCCUCUACCUCUGUUACCUCGUCAGUAAGAUAGAGAUAACAGGACCUAACUUCGAGGGUUGUUGGAAAGACCAAGUGAGUAAAGGCAUGUUGUGCCCUUAGAGCCUGGCACGUGUUCAUCACUGCUAUUAUUUCUGGCUACUCGGUGCCAGGACAGGGGCCUCAGCUGAGGGCCCCCCAGAGCCUGGCAGGCCCAGUGAAGGAGUGAGAUGGGGAGGCCACGACUCCUCCCCAGUCAGCAGCUGUCCUGUGGCCAUGGGGGCCUGGUGAGGCCAGAUCUUCAGGUUGUUCUAGAAAACUGAGGCUGGAGUUUGGAGUUUGACCCGCUUGGAGGCUCUCUCAGCAGCGGGCAUAUAGGAGGAAGGGUCACUGCUGUCUCCGGAAGCUCUUGGCUGCAAAGAGAGAGGAUCCCGGGUAUCUCCCUCCUUACAACCACCGCCACCUCCUAGUGCCUUAGAAGCCACUGACAGCCCCCAGGGCAGGUGAGCCCUGCAUCUGGAAUAAGGAUCCAGAGGUCUCGUUCAGGACCAUGGAGAGCGGCACCAGCAGCCCUCAGCCUCCACAGUUAGAUCCCCUGGAUGCGUUUCCCCAGAAGGGCUUGGAGCCUGGGGACAUCGCGGUGCUAGUUCUGUACUUCCUCUUUGUCCUGGCUGUUGGACUAUGGUCCACAGUGAAGACCAAAAGAGACACAGUGAAAGGCUACUUCCUGGCUGGAGGGGACAUGGUGUGGUGGCCAGUGGGUGCAUCCUUGUUUGCCAGCAAUGUUGGAAGUGGACAUUUCAUUGGCCUGGCAGGGUCAGGUGCUGCUACGGGCAUUUCUGUAUCAGCUUAUGAACUUAAUGGCUUGUUUUCUGUGCUGAUGUUGGCCUGGAUCUUCCUACCCAUCUACAUUGCUGGUCAGGUCACCACGAUGCCAGAAUACCUACGGAAGCGCUUCGGUGGCAUCAGAAUCCCCAUCAUCCUGGCUGUACUCUACCUAUUUAUCUACAUCUUCACCAAGAUCUCGGUAGACAUGUAUGCAGGUGCCAUCUUCAUCCAGCAGUCUUUGCACCUGGAUCUGUACCUGGCCAUAGUUGGGCUACUGGCCAUCACUGCUGUAUACACGGUUGCUGGUGGCCUGGCUGCUGUGAUCUACACGGAUGCCCUGCAGACGCUGAUCAUGCUUAUAGGAGCGCUCACCUUGAUGGGCUACAGUUUCGCCGCGGUUGGUGGGAUGGAAGGACUGAAGGAGAAGUACUUCUUGGCCCUGGCUAGCAACCGGAGUGAGAACAGCAGCUGCGGGCUGCCCCGGGAAGAUGCCUUCCAUAUUUUCCGAGAUCCGCUGACAUCUGAUCUCCCGUGGCCGGGGGUCCUAUUUGGAAUGUCCAUCCCAUCCCUCUGGUACUGGUGCACGGAUCAGGUGAUUGUCCAGCGGACUCUGGCUGCCAAGAACCUGUCCCAUGCCAAAGGAGGUGCUCUGAUGGCUGCAUACCUGAAGGUGCUGCCCCUCUUCAUAAUGGUGUUCCCUGGGAUGGUCAGCCGCAUCCUCUUCCCAGAUCAAGUGGCCUGUGCAGAUCCAGAGAUCUGCCAGAAGAUCUGCAGCAACCCCUCAGGCUGUUCGGACAUCGCGUAUCCCAAACUCGUGCUGGAACUCCUGCCCACAGGGCUCCGUGGGCUGAUGAUGGCUGUGAUGGUGGCGGCUCUCAUGUCCUCCCUCACCUCCAUCUUUAACAGUGCCAGCACCAUCUUCACCAUGGACCUCUGGAAUCACCUCCGGCCUCGGGCAUCUGAGAAGGAGCUCAUGAUUGUGGGCAGGGUGUUUGUGCUGCUGCUGGUCCUGGUCUCCAUCCUCUGGAUCCCUGUGGUCCAGGCCAGCCAGGGCGGCCAGCUCUUCAUCUAUAUCCAGUCCAUCAGCUCCUACCUGCAGCCGCCUGUGGCGGUGGUCUUCAUCAUGGGAUGUUUCUGGAAGAGGACCAAUGAAAAGGGUGCCUUCUGGGGCCUGAUCUCGGGCCUGCUCCUGGGCUUGGUUAGGCUGGUCCUGGACUUUAUUUACGUGCAGCCUCGAUGCGACCAGCCAGAUGAGCGCCCGGUCCUGGUGAAGAGCAUUCACUACCUCUACUUCUCCAUGAUCCUGUCCACGGUCACCCUCAUCACUGUCUCCACCGUGAGCUGGUUCACAGAGCCACCCUCCAAGGAGAUGGUCAGCCACCUGACCUGGUUUACUCGUCACGACCCCGUGGUCCAGAAGGAACAAGCACCACCAGCAGCUCCCUUGUCUCUUACCCUCUCUCAGAACGGGAUGCCAGAGGCCAGCAGCAGCAGCAGCGUCCAGUUCGAGAUGGUUCAAGAAAACACGUCUAAAACCCACAGCUGUGACAUGACCCCAAAGCAGUCCAAAGUGGUGAAGGCCAUCCUGUGGCUCUGUGGAAUACAGGAGAAGGGCAAGGAAGAGCUCCCGGCCAGAGCAGAAGCCAUCAUAGUUUCCCUGGAAGAAAACCCCUUGGUGAAGACCCUCCUGGACGUCAACCUCAUUUUCUGCGUGAGCUGCGCCAUCUUUAUCUGGGGCUAUUUUGCUUAGUGUGGGGUGAACCCAGGGGUCCAAACUCUGUUUCUCUUCAGUGCUCCAUUUUUUUAAUGAAAGAAAAAAUAAUAAAGCUUUUGUUUACCACAA